UCCGCAGUCCCGGUUCUAAAGUCCCCAGUCACCCACCCGGACUCACAUUCUCCCCAGAGGCCGAGAUGCGGGUCAUGGCGCCCCGAGCCCUCCUCCUGCUGCUCUCGGGAGGCCUGGCCCUGACCGAGACCUGGGCCUGCUCCCACUCCAUGAGGUAUUUCGACACCGCCGUGUCCCGGCCCGGCCGCGGAGAGCCCCGCUUCAUCUCAGUGGGCUACGUGGACGACACGCAGUUCGUGCGGUUCGACAGCGACGCCGCGAGUCCGAGAGGGGAGCCGCGGGCGCCGUGGGUGGAGCAGGAGGGGCCGGAGUAUUGGGACCGGGAGACACAGAACUACAAGCGCCAGGCACAGGCUGACCGAGUGAGCCUGCGGAACCUGCGCGGCUACUACAACCAGAGCGAGGACGGGUCUCACACCCUCCAGAGGAUGUAUGGCUGCGACCUGGGGCCCGACGGGCGCCUCCUCCGCGGGUAUGACCAGUCCGCCUACGACGGCAAGGAUUACAUCGCCCUGAACGAGGACCUGCGCUCCUGGACCGCCGCGGACACCGCGGCUCAGAUCACCCAGCGCAAGUUGGAGGCGGCCCGUGCGGCGGAGCAGCUGAGAGCCUACCUGGAGGGCACGUGCGUGGAGUGGCUCCGCAGAUACCUGGAGAACGGGAAGGAGACGCUGCAGCGCGCAGAACCCCCAAAGACACACGUGACCCACCACCCCCUCUCUGACCAUGAGGCCACCCUGAGGUGCUGGGCCCUGGGCUUCUACCCUGCGGAGAUCACACUGACCUGGCAGCGGGAUGGGGAGGACCAGACCCAGGACACCGAGCUUGUGGAGACCAGGCCAGCAGGAGAUGGAACCUUCCAGAAGUGGGCAGCUGUGGUGGUGCCUUCUGGACAAGAGCAGAGAUACACGUGCCAUAUGCAGCACGAGGGGCUGCAAGAGCCCCUCACCCUGAGCUGGGAGCCAUCUUCCCAGCCCACCAUCCCCAUCAUGGGCAUCGUUGCUGGCCUGGCUGUCCUGGUUGUCCUAGCUGUCCUUGGAGCUGUGGUCACCGCUAUGAUGUGUAGGAGGAAGAGCUCAGGUGGAAAAGGAGGGAGCUGCUCUCAGGCUGCGUGCAGCAACAGUGCCCAGGGCUCUGAUGAGUCUCUCAUCACUUGUAAAGCCUGAGACAGCUGCCUGUGUGGGACUGAGAUGCAGGAUUUCUUCACACCUCUCCUUUGUGACUUCAAGAGCCUCUGGCAUCUCUUUCUGCAAAGGCGUCUGAAUGUGUCUGCGUUCCUGUUAGCAUAAUGUGAGGAGGUGGAGAGACAGCCCACCCCCGUGUCCACCGUGACCCCUGUCCCCACACUGACCUGUGUUCCCUCCCCGAUCAUCUUUCCUGUUCCAGAGAGGUGGGGCUGGAUGUCUCCAUCUCUGUCUCAAAUUCAUGGUGCACUGAGCUGCAACUUCUUACUUCCCUAAUGAAGUUAAGAACCUGAAUAUAAAUUUGUGUUCUCAAAUAUUUGCUAUGAAGCGUUGAUGGAUUAAUUAAAUAAGUCAAUUCCUAGAAGUUGAGAGAGCAAAUAAAGACCUGAGAACCUUCCAGAA